AGGAGAAGUUUUCUGGUUUUUUAGCAAAAGAGACUGACCAUGUGUAAACAUUCUUUAAACUGUUUCCUCACUGUGGUUUUACUGUGUGGAGGGCUAAAUUUUAAAAGUAAAUAUAAUGUUAUAACAAUUUGCUUAUUACCAGCAAGUUUUUAAUAUUGACCAAUGUUUUAUGUAUUGGGUGGCUUAAUGGUUUUAACUGGAGAAAACUGAUUAGGAAGACAGUUAUUCACUUCUGUUUGCUGAACUGGAAGGAAGUCAUAAAAAAAGAAAACUUCAGAAGCUGACUUUUUUCAAAGAAGAUAUGAGAAGUUUAGAUAUAACUUGUGAAAUUUAGGUCUCUCUCAUGAGAUUGCCAAAGGCACAGUUAAAUUCUCUGGGAGGCCCAAUUGAUUAUUGUGUAAAGCUGUUUAAAUUUUCAAGGAUCUUCUAAAAUGCAUUUCUAGUUUUUGAUACAAAAGUUAAUUGAUUUCAGAUGUCAGCUUGUGUCUUAUGGUGAUGAAAGUGGUUGAGGAAAUACAGGUAAAAAUAAAGCGUACUAUAUUAAUUGGAAAACAUUGAUGGAGUUGGAGCUGUCAUUGAGUGGAUUCUCUAGGGAGUCUUAGUAGGUCACGUUUUUCCAGGCAUUGGGGCAUUCUGGGAUCCAACAGUUAAAUCUGUGAAGGGACAAAUAGAGAUGUCACCAGAAUCAGGAGAUUGAGAUUUAUGCCCAAAAGUCCAGAUGCUUUCUUGGGAGAUACCCCAAAGAAAUGAUAUCUACUAACAUUUCUGCCUUUAGUUUAUCAGAAAGAAGUUGAGAGAAGAUCAGGAAUAAGGCAUUUCUUAUAAUAAGAGUAAUUGUAUUUUUUUGAAGGUACUCCUUUCUUAGUGGCUUCUAGAAAUACUGUCAUUGAUUUUUCAUAUCAAUAGUUUAAUUCACUGAGUUAAGAAAACUGUUAUUUUUUAAAAAACAAAACAAAACACAAAGAAAAACCCAUGGGGUUUUGGGGCUUAGAAACUUUGUGUUAUAAGAAGUAUAAUAGCUAUGUUCUGCUAAUUUAUUUAUAUAACAAAACUUUUUAAAUUAAAUAUUUGGAUUGUAGUAGAGGUACUUGCCUUUAAAAAGUACUUCAGGCCGGGUGUGUUGGCUCAUUCCUGUAAUCCCAGCACUUUGGUAGGCCGAGGCGGGUGGAUCACUUGAGGUCAGGAGUUCGAGACCAGCCUGCCCAACAUGGUGAAACCCUGUCUCUACUAAAACGGUACAAAAAUUGGCCAGGUGUGGUGCUGGGCAUCUGGAGUCCCAGCUACUUAGGGGGCUGAGGUGGGAGAAUCGCUUGAACCUGUGAGGCAGAGUUUGCAGUGAGCUGAUAUUGUGUCACUACCCUCCAGCCUGGGGGACAGAGCAAGACUUCAUCUCAAAAAAAUAAAAAUAAAUAAAUAAAAGGUACUUCAGCUGAGGCAGUUCAUGCAGUAGUGUAUCAUUUUGGAAUGUGGGUAAGCACCCCUGAAUUUACAUGGCCUGGAAAUUUUUUAUAUUUGAUUUUCUCAAAGUGCAGUAUAACAUACUCAUCUCCUUGUGAACAGAAAUGUUUGAGGAUGGGUUAAAUGAACUGUAGAAAGCAUCUCAGAAAAAGGUGUUAUGCAAGGCAUAAUUAUUUUCCAAGUGCUAUCUGAGCAGCUUUCACCAAUCAAAGCUUCCUUGAAAUAGAGAUUACAAUCAAAGUUCAUCUGUAUACUAUUGUGUUUGGAGUACAUGCCAACAUUCCAACUUGAAGUUGCUUUGAGGGAAAAGUUCUUCAAAUUCAUCAGUGUUGUGGGGAAAUGUGAUUUAAAUUCUGAUUACUGGAAGCCUUAUUACAGAGGAGGUGGCAAGCAGGUGAGUUGAGCUGUUCAGGAUGUCUGUUUCUUAUUUGUUCUUUUAAGAUAUUGCAAAGAAACUGAUUGUGGUGUCUAUCUGUUGCUAGUUCUUCUCCAGCAUCAAUUCCCAUUUUCUUCUUAUAGUCUGGAAUUUCCUUUGGGAAACCUCCUAUAUUCUUUGUCUAUGUAGUUCAAGAGGGGCUGCUCACACCCCAACCCAUGCUGCAAUCAAAAAGGGGUUCAUCUGCUGCCCACAGUGACUAACUGAUGAUUAAUUAAUCAAAAUUGUUCAAAUGAAAUUCAGUUCCUGGCAUUUUUGUUGAAAUUAUUUAAAAGAAGACUUUACUUUUUCUUCUGGAGUUUUUUUAGCCAAUAAUAAGCAAGAUCACCGGUGUUAGUGGUAGUUCUUUUGCUACCAUCACGUUUGAGAGGAAGGCAGAGCUUGGAGCUGGAGAUACAGAAUCCUGAGGACCUAGUCUGAAUACCUGAUCAGUUAGGCAAGCCAGUGAACUCUUCUGCUUUGUGUAAACCAGUUUGAGUUGGAUUUCUGUCACUUGUAACUGAAAUAGACCUGAUUGACACACCCUUGUAAGUUUAGUGUCGGAACUGCUUUCACCCCAAGAGCUAACUUUUGUUAUAUGUAUGUCAUUGAUUUUUGUUGUGGUGGUUGUUGUUAGUAUUUUUCUUAAAAAAUAAAAUAGGGGUUUUUAUCAUAAUAAAAAUAGAAAUUACUAAAUAUAAAAUGCUGUACUAGGAAAAAAAAACCCUGAUAUUUGUGCUCAAAGGUGACAUCAGAUGCCUGUGUCUAGUUUGGGAGUCAGGGUGACAGUACCUCAUAAAAUAAGUUGAAGGAACAUUUCUUCUUUUUGUAUUUUGUUAAAUAAUUUGUAGUUACCUGUUCUUUGAAUGUCAUAAAAUUAUCUGUAAAACUAUCUAAUCAUAGGUUGAUUAUCUCCUUAGUUUUUAUUUGGGUAUGUUCUACUUUGUUUUUCUAACUUCUUGAGUUGGAUACUUAGUAUAUUUUCUUUAUUUACUAAAAAGCUUGUAAAAUUAUUUUAAAAAAUCCUUGUCUCACAAUUCUUCUCCUAUCAAUAAUGAUUUGAAAUUUUUCCAUGUAUAUGAAACACCUCCAAGGACAGAUAAUGUCCUUGAUUAGCAGAGUAGCUGGGUUAUUACAGUCUGUCUCAAAGAGUUGAAGGGAAAAGCCUACAUAUAUUCUUUACAAAAAGAGAGGUUAGAUGUGCUUGGGAGCAAUCAUCCUGCCAGUAAAGCUGCGUGAGGGUUUUACCUUACUGAUGUGGCCUCCCUGCGUUGGCAGGUAUUACUGCUUCCAGAUUUGGUCACAGCAUGGGACAAAGGAAUAUACAGACCUCCUUCCUGCCUUUGAAUAAUUAGCAUCAGCAGAGUAUCCUGAAUAGUGAUUAGAUAUAAACAAAGCAAACAGAUAGAGAACCUGGAGAGAGUUAGCUUUUAGGAAUGCUUUAGAAAUGAUCACCAACUCUGUCAAAUGUGGAGGCAUUUGUGGAUUUUGAUAGUAUUUAUUUAUUUAUUUUGGCCUAGCAGCAUUUACUUUUUUUGGAAGACAUCCACCCUGUACUGCAAGUGAUGGCCCUACUGGCUGUAUAUACAGAUGGGCAACUACGAUUCCAAAUAUCACACAGCUAUAGUAGGGUUCACCCAAAUGGAGCCCUUUGCCUCCAGGGUCUUUUUCUUCCUGUGAAGAGAAUUUGAAUCAGUGCUCUAGUGGUAAUAAUACAAAUAUUGCUAUCUUAGAAGUACUUAAACCUCUAUAUUUUCUUAUUCCAGGUGGUUUUCCUGAAAUCAAACUCUGAUUUCCAGGGAUAAAAAGACAACACGUGAAAAACCCCUGGUAUUCUCAGAUUUGACAUGACUUUCACUGUAUACAUGGCUUUAACUCUAUUUAAUAGAAUGUUCCUGUGAAGCUGAAAACCGUGCUAUCAAGACUAAUCAGGACCUUCUCCCAGAAACUCCAUGGACGCACAUUUUCUACAAUGAUUUUUGGGGGACUCUUCUAACCCACAGUGGCAGCCACAAGUCCUACCGGCCACUCUGCACUCUUUCUUUUCGCCUGAACCAUGCCAUUGGAGGGUUGAAUCCCUGGAGCUACCAUCUUGUCAAUGUCCUGUUGCAUGCAGCAGUCACUGGUCUCUUCACAAGCUUCUCCAAGAUCCUCCUUGGUGAUGGAUACUGGACAUUCAUGGCUGGCUUGAUGUUUGCUUCUCACCCCAUUCACACGGAGGCAGUGGCAGGAAUCGUGGGACGAGCCGAUGUCGGGGCCAGUCUCUUCUUUCUCCUCUCCUUGCUCUGCUACAUUAAACACUGUUCUACAAGAGGCUACUCAGCCAGAACCUGGGGCUGGUUCCUGGGGUCAGGACUGUGCGCAGGAUGCAGCAUGUUGUGGAAGGAACAAGGAGUGACUGUUCUCGCAGUUUCAGCAGUUUAUGAUGUCUUUGUCUUUCACAGGCUGAAAAUAAAACAGAUAUUACCUACCAUUUACAAAAGGAAGAACUUGUCGCUUUUCCUAAGCAUUAGUUUGUUAAUUUUCUGGGGUUCCUCCCUUUUGGGUGCCCGGUUAUACUGGAUGGGAAACAAACCACCAAGCUUUUCCAACUCGGACAACCCCGCUGCUGAUUCGGACAGCCUCCUCACCCGCACUCUCACCUUCUUCUACUUGCCAACCAAGAACCUCUGGCUGUUGCUAUGUCCAGAUACCCUCAGUUUUGAUUGGUCAAUGGAUGCUGUGCCUCUGCUCAAAACAGUUUGUGACUGGAGAAACCUACACACUGUGGCCUUCUAUACUGGACUCCUUCUCCUUGCCUACUAUGGUUUGAAGAGCCCGAGCGUAGACAGAGAAUGCAAUGGGAAAACUGUAACAAAUGGCAAGCAGAAUGCAAAUGGACAUAGCUGCCUUUCAGAUGUGGAGUACCAGAACUCAGAGACUAAGUCCAGCUUUGCAUCCAAAGUAGAAAAUGGCAUUAAAAACGAUGUAUCACAGAGAACCCAGCUUCCUUCUACGGAGAACAUUGUUGUUCUGUCUUUAUCUUUGUUAAUCAUACCCUUUGUUCCUGCCACGAACCUGUUUUUCUAUGUCGGCUUUGUAAUUGCAGAGCGAGUAUUAUAUAUUCCUAGUAUGGGCUUCUGCCUACUGAUUACAGUGGGUGCUAGAGCCCUUUAUGUCAAAGUCCAAAAGCGGUUCCUCAAGAGCUUGAUUUUUUAUGCUACAGCUACACUAAUUGUUUUUUAUGGACUCAAGACUGCGAUCAGGAAUGGAGACUGGCAGAAUGAGGAAAUGCUUUAUAGAUCAGGGAUAAAAGUAAACCCAGCUAAAGCAUGGGGUAACCUUGGAAAUGUUCUGAAGAGUCAGAGCAAAAUUUCUGAAGCUGAAAGCGCCUAUAGAAAUGCUUUGUACUACCGCAGCAACAUGGCUGACAUGCUUUAUAAUUUAGGGCUACUUCUCCAGGAGAACAGCAGGUUUGCAGAAGCACUACAUUAUUAUAAAUUGGCCAUUGGGAGCAGGCCUACCCUGGCUUCUGCAUAUUUAAAUACCGGUAUUAUUCUAAUGAACCAAGGAAGGACGGAAGAAGCCCGACGGACAUUCUUAAAGUGUUCGGAGAUCCCAGAUGAAAACCUAAAGGACCCUCAUGCACACAAGAGCUCUGUUACCAGUUGUUUGUACAACCUAGGAAAGCUGUAUCAUGAGCAGGGACACUAUGAGGAAGCCCUUAGUGUAUACAAGGAAGCAAUUCAGAAAAUGCCAAGGCAGUUUGCCCCACAGAGCUUGUACAACAUGAUGGGUGAAGCAUAUAUGCGUUUAAGCAAACUCCCCGAAGCAGAGCAUUGGUAUAUGGAAUCACUGAGAUCCAAGACUGACCACAUCCCUGCUCAUCUCACCUAUGGGAAGCUGCUAGCUCUAACAGGUCGUAAGAGUGAGGCUGAAAAGCUCUUCUUGAAGGCUAUUGAGCUGGAUCCCACCAAAGGAAACUGUUACAUGCAUUAUGGUCAGUUUCUUCUGGAAGAAGCUCGUCUCAUAGAAGCAGCUGAGAUGGCAAAAAAAGCAGCUGAACUAGACAGCACAGAGUUUGAUGUUGUCUUCAAUGCUGCCCACAUGCUCAGACAGGCUAGCCUCAAUGAAGCAGCUGAGAAGUAUUAUGAUCUGGCAGCCAGGCUGAGGCCUAAUUAUCCGGCUGCUUUGAUGAACCUGGGAGCCAUUCUGCACCUCAAUGGCAGACUCCAGAAGGCCGAGGCCAACUACCUGCGGGCCCUGCAGCUCAAGCCAGACGAUGUCAUCACACAGUCCAAUCUCCGCAAACUGUGGAACAUCAUGGAAAAACAAGGCUUAAAGACUUCUAAGACCUGACACAGGAGGCAGAAGCCCAUCCUCCUCCAUUUUUAAAAGCUGGCUUCCUUAGCAGACAGAACUUCCCAGCAGUGCUAUGACAAGAGCUGGUGUUAGACUUCAAGACCAGGGCAGAGGUCAUUGAGGUCACUACCGCUUCUGGAAGAAUCCACUUUGCUGUAGGCACAGCUGUUAACACCAAAAAGGGGAAAGCCGGAAACCUCCUGGAGGAUGUCAUUGUUACCCAUAGACUGUAAACCAGAGCACUUAAAACAGAACCUUUUGGCAUUCUUAAAAAGGGAGGGGUGGGUGUGUAAGUCACAGAUUUUGUUCAUUUUCUGAAAGCUAAUUUCAAAAUUAUGUUGUUCCUUAAACACUGUGAGAGGAAGUCAGAGUGUCCAUUCAGGCAUGGCAAACAAUUAGGGUUAAGUGUUACGAGGGAGUGAUAAACACGUAGUGUGAGUCCCAGUGAGCCGCCGGUUGUCCUAACGCUGCUGUCUUCCCUGUUUGGGACAGCCUGCUUAUCAAUUUCUGAAGCUUAGAACACUUUUUUUAAUACUGUGUCAAGAUCUGUCAGAAUCUGCUAUGUUUCUUGACCAGUGCACAUAAUGUUUUAUGAUUUGGAUGUCAGAGGCUUCAUUCUUUUGGACAUCAUUUGCUUUUUAUGUUCUGAAAAGGAUAUGGAGAGUAGAGCUAACCAUACUUCACACUCGAGUUGUAUGAGGGACUGGGGAGGCCUUAUAUGUGUCAGGCAGGCAUUUUUUAAAUUUUAAUAUCGUCAAUAUUUUCCCCCAAACUGCCCAGUAGAAUUCAUUGUAUUAAUUCUUUUGAAAUUACCUUUGAAAAUAGCUAUUCCUGGAGAAUGUGCAAGCUUACAUAAGGAUAAAGGACAGGGGAGGAGUUUGUAAGCCUUGCAGUUCCAAUAACUAACCAACAGGUUAUUAGACAAAAGGGAAGGUGUUUUGUGCUUCUCAGAUGUUGCUGGUUUAGGAGUGUGUGAUGAUGCUUGCCAGUGAUUUUGUGUUUUGGAAAGGGUAGGUAUCGAAUGUUAAUCACUUUCUAAUGGGUACCUAAACAGCAAUGCUGAUAAAUGUUCAAGGAAUUAUUUUCAUCUUAGUUUGUUCUUCUCAAAAGGCAUCAAAAACAACUUAUUUGAAGCUGCAAUAGAGUGUAGCAUUAGCCUGCAUGUUUCUAGGUCUUCUGCCAAGUGCUUUUCUCAGUUGAAAACUAUUUUUCACUAGCAAAAUUGGUAUUUUAUUUCAUUACCUGUUAGUAACUACUUCAAUGAUCAUUUCACAAGAAAAAGACUAUAAAUUAAGUAGAGAACAACAUUUUUAUUGAACAUUUUUGGCUUGCAAUCAAACUUUGCCACUAAAAAUUAACUUCAUAAAACACUAGUCCGUUAUCAACUUCUUCACAGAGAAAGUAGCUAUACUAUACCCUACAUAUUUAUUUAUUUAUUAUUCUACUAUAGCAGAAUAACAAAACUUGAUGCAUUAAGCCAGUUCUUUGCAACUGAAAAUUACCUGUUUCUCCUUCCCUUUCACACUCCAUGUAUAUAUGAUCAGCCUCUCCAUUAAAAAGAAGCUGGACAUGCAAAUACAUCAUAUUAUGUUUUCUCCAUAUUUUAUGUUUUUCUAUGUAUCUGAAUACAGUGGGAUAAAUAAUUGAAAGUAGUGUUCCUAUGGCAUUAGUGUUUUUGUGAGAAGGGUAAAUGUAGUGAGAAAGGUUUUUUCAUGGCAUUAAUAAGAAAGCCCUUCUGUAAUAUAUAUAUUAUUUUGUAAACAUUUCACUGAAGGGCCAAAAGUUAAAUUAUAACUAAAUCACUGUGUUUUCAGAAUGAUAUUUAACAACAAACCCGUGGUCAAACCAAAAUAGUGGGUUGAAGUGUAUUAUUCAUCUUUUAGUGCAUUGGCAAUUGCAAAAAAAAAAAAGGAAUUUAAUAUAAGGCUAUAGAGAUUAAUUCAGUGUCUAACAUUUGUAUUUAUUUAAAUAGUUAUUGACCUAUGAUGACUUUCUAGUCUUAACAUUUUAUCUUUUUAUUGUUGUUGUUCUUCCUUUCAAAGAUGUGGUUCUUAAUAGGUUCACUGAAUGCACAGUUGAGGCACUUCUUGUGACACCAGUUCCCAAGUAGCGUUAAUAAUUGGGCCUGUGUCAUAAAAUGCACGGAUCAUUAAUAACUAAAUGUCCCUGACACUUUUCACUACAGGGCUGGACUUAGUAACUGACCAACUUCGGGGGGAGGGUUGGGGCAAGGGGGGGUGGGCGUUAGAACAUGAUCAAAAAAUGUCUCCGCUCAGGGAUUUAUGGUGGAUUAUUGCAGACAGUGCUAAAAAUAUAGAGCACAAGACAAGUUUACUAAAUUAAAAUUUUAUUUUUUGAGAAACUGUUAUUUGUAUAAAUUAUCAAGAUUUGUAGGCUUUCCUUUUGUAGAAAUAAUUGUUUUAUGUGCCAGAGAAUUUCAAUUUUGUUUUCAACAAUAAAGCAUUGAUAAGAAA